ACCGCUUUCGCUUUCCCUUCGCGGUGCCCACUCCACUCCUUGUGCGGCGCUAGGCCCCCCGUCCCGGUCAUGGCCAUGCUCAGGGUCCAGCCCGAGGCCCAAGCCAAGGUGGAUGUGUUUCGUGAAGACCUCUGUACCAAGACAGAGAACCUGCUCGGGAGCUAUUUCCCCAAGAAGAUUUCUGAGCUGGAUGCAUUUUUAAAGGAGCCAGCUCUCAAUGAAGCCAACUUGAGCAAUCUGAAGGCCCCAUUGGACAUCCCAGUGCCUGAUCCAGUCAAGGAGAAAGAGAAAGAGGAGCGGAAGAAACAGCAGGAGAAGGAAGACAAGGAUGAAAAGAAGAAGGGGGAGGAUGAAGACAAAGGUCCUCCCUGUGGCCCAGUGAACUGCAAUGAAAAGAUCGUGGUCCUUCUGCAGCGCUUGAAGCCUGAGAUCAAGGAUGUCAUUGAGCAGCUCAACCUGGUCACCACCUGGUUGCAGCUGCAGAUACCUCGGAUUGAGGAUGGUAACAAUUUUGGAGUGGCUGUCCAGGAGAAGGUGUUUGAGCUGAUGACCAGCCUCCACACCAAGCUAGAAGGCUUCCACACUCAAAUCUCUAAGUAUUUCUCUGAGCGUGGUGAUGCAGUGACUAAAGCAGCCAAGCAGCCCCAUGUGGGUGAUUAUCGGCAGCUGGUGCACGAGCUGGAUGAGGCAGAGUACCGGGACAUCCGGCUGAUGGUCAUGGAGAUCCGCAAUGCUUAUGUGAGGAGGCAAGGGCAGGGCAGGGGUGGGCAGAGGCAGCUUUCCCAGGCCACCCACUCCCUGACCCUGCAGGCUAGGGGUUAAGGGUGACAAAGCUCAGCUUCUCCACAAGGCUAGAAAUGGGGCACAGAGCCACUGGAGGCCUCUGACUGACCUCUACUCCCUGGCCCUGUAGGCUGUGUUAUAUGACAUCAUCCUGAAGAACUUCGAGAAGCUCAAGAAGCCCAGGGGAGAAACAAAGGGAAUGAUCUAUUGAGAGCCCUCUCUCCCAUUCUGUGAUGAGUACAGCAGAGACCUUCCUGCUUUUUACUGGGGACUCCAGAUUUUCCCCAAACUUGCUUCUGUUGAGAUUUUUCCCUCACCUUGCCUCUCAGGCACAAUAAAUAUAGUUAUACCACUGCC